AGCGACGUCGAGGCGCUCAUGGUUGCAGGCGGGCGCCGCCGUUCAGUUCAGGGUCUGAGCCUGGAGGAGUGAGCCAGGCAGUGAGACUGGCUCGGGCGGGCCGGGACGCGUCGUUGCAGCAGCGGCUCCCAGCUCCCAGCCAGGAUUCCGCGCGCCCCUUCACGCGCCCUGCUCCUGAACUUCAGCUCCUGCACAGUCCUCCCCACCGCAAGGCUCAAGGCGCCGCCGGCGUGGACCGCGCACGGCCUCUAGGUCUCCUCGCCAGGACAGCAACCUCUCCCCUGGCCCUCAUGGGCACCGUCAGCUCCAGGCGGUCCUGGUGGCCGCUGCCACUGCUGCUGCUGCUGCUGCUGCUCCUGGGUCCCGCGGGCGCCCGUGCGCAGGAGGACGAGGACGGCGACUACGAGGAGCUGGUGCUAGCCUUGCGUUCCGAGGAGGACGGCCUGGCCGAAGCACCCGAGCACGGAACCACAGCCACCUUCCACCGCUGCGCCAAGGUGCGGGUGUAGGGAUGGGAGGCCGGGGCGAACCCGCAGCCGGGACGGUGCGGUGCUGUUUCCUCUCGGGCCUCAGUUUCCCCCCAUGUAAGAGAGGAAGUGGAGUGCAGGUCGCCGAGGGCUCUUCGCUUGGCACGAUCUUGGGGACUGCAGGCAAGGCGGCGGGGGAGGACGGGUAGUGGGGAGCACGGUGGAGAGCGGGGACGGCCGGCUCUUUGGGGACUUGCUGGGGCGUGCGGCUGCGCUAUUCAGUGGGAAGGUUCGCGGGGUUGGGAGACCCGGAGGCCGAGGAAGGGCGAGCAGAGCACUGCCAGGAUAUCCUGCCCAGAUUUCCCAGUUUCUGCCUCGCCGCGGCACAGGAUCCGUGGAGGUUGCCUGGCACCUACGUGGUGGUGCUGAAGGAGGAGACCCACCUCUCGCAGUCAGAGCGCACUGCCCGCCGCCUGCAGGCCCAGGCUGCCCGCCGGGGAUACCUCACCAAGAUCCUGCAUGUCUUCCAUGGCCUUCUUCCUGGCUUCCUGGUGAAGAUGAGUGGCGACCUGCUGGAGCUGGCCUUGAAGUUGCCCCAUGUCGACUACAUCGAGGAGGACUCCUCUGUCUUUGCCCAGAGCAUCCCGUGGAACCUGGAGCGGAUUACCCCUCCACGGUACCGGGCGGAUGAAUACCAGCCCCCCGACGGAGGCAGCCUGGUGGAGGUGUAUCUCCUAGACACCAGCAUACAGAGUGACCACCGGGAAAUCGAGGGCAGGGUCAUGGUCACCGACUUCGAGAAUGUGCCCGAGGAGGACGGGACCCGCUUCCACAGACAGGCCAGCAAGUGUGACAGUCAUGGCACCCACCUGGCAGGGGUGGUCAGCGGCCGGGAUGCCGGCGUGGCCAAGGGUGCCAGCAUGCGCAGCCUGCGCGUGCUCAACUGCCAAGGGAAGGGCACGGUUAGCGGCACCCUCAUAGGCCUGGAGUUUAUUCGGAAAAGCCAGCUGGUCCAGCCUGUGGGGCCACUGGUGGUGCUGCUGCCCCUGGCGGGUGGGUACAGCCGCGUCCUCAACGCCGCCUGCCAGCGCCUGGCGAGGGCUGGGGUCGUGCUGGUCACCGCUGCCGGCAACUUCCGGGACGAUGCCUGCCUCUACUCCCCAGCCUCAGCUCCCGAGGUCAUCACAGUUGGGGCCACCAAUGCCCAAGACCAGCCGGUGACCCUGGGGACUUUGGGGACCAACUUUGGCCGCUGUGUGGACCUCUUUGCCCCAGGGGAGGACAUCAUUGGUGCCUCCAGCGACUGCAGCACCUGCUUUGUGUCACAGAGUGGGACAUCACAGGCUGCUGCCCACGUGGCUGGCAUUGCAGCCAUGAUGCUGUCUGCCGAGCCGGAGCUCACCCUGGCCGAGUUGAGGCAGAGACUGAUCCACUUCUCUGCCAAAGAUGUCAUCAAUGAGGCCUGGUUCCCUGAGGACCAGCGGGUACUGACCCCCAACCUGGUGGCCGCCCUGCCCCCCAGCACCCAUGGGGCAGGUUGGCAGCUGUUUUGCAGGACUGUAUGGUCAGCACACUCGGGGCCUACACGGAUGGCCACAGCCGUCGCCCGCUGCGCCCCAGAUGAGGAGCUGCUGAGCUGCUCCAGUUUCUCCAGGAGUGGGAAGCGGCGGGGCGAGCGCAUGGAGGCCCAAGGGGGCAAGCUGGUCUGCCGGGCCCACAACGCUUUUGGGGGUGAGGGUGUCUACGCCAUUGCCAGGUGCUGCCUGCUACCCCAGGCCAACUGCAGCGUCCACACAGCUCCACCAGCUGAGGCCAGCAUGGGGACCCGUGUCCACUGCCACCAACAGGGCCACGUCCUCACAGGCUGCAGCUCCCACUGGGAGGUGGAGGACCUUGGCACCCACAAGCCGCCUGUGCUGAGGCCACGAGGUCAGCCCAACCAGUGCGUGGGCCACAGGGAGGCCAGCAUCCACGCUUCCUGCUGCCAUGCCCCAGGUCUGGAAUGCAAAGUCAAGGAGCAUGGAAUCCCGGCCCCUCAGGAGCAGGUGACCGUGGCCUGCGAGGAGGGCUGGACCCUGACUGGCUGCAGUGCCCUCCCUGGGACCUCCCACGUCCUGGGGGCCUACGCCGUAGACAACACGUGUGUAGUCAGGAGCCGGGACGUCAGCACUACAGGCAGCACCAGCGAAGGGGCCGUGACAGCCGUUGCCAUCUGCUGCCGGAGCCGGCACCUGGCGCAGGCCUCCCAGGAGCUCCAGUGACAGCCCCAUCCCAGGAUGGGUGUCUGGGGAGGGUCAAGGGCUGGGGCUGAGCUUUAAAAUGGUUCCGACUUGUCCCUCUCUCAGCCCUCCAUGGCCUGGCACGAGGGGAUGGGGAUGCUUCCGCCUUUCCGGGGCUGCUGGCCUGGCCCUUGAGUGGGGCAGCCUCCUUGCCUGGAACUCACUCACUCUGGGUGCCUCCUCCCCAGGUGGAGGUGCCAGGAAGCUCCCUCCCUCACUGUGGGGCAUUUCACCAUUCAAACAGGUCGAGCUGUGCUCGGGUGCUGCCAGCUGCUCCCAAUGUGCCGAUGUCCGUGGGCAGAAUGACUUUUAUUGAGCUCUUGUUCCGUGCCAGGCAUUCAAUCCUCAGGUCUCCACCAAGGAGGCAGGAUUCUUCCCAUGGAUAGGGGAGGGGGCGGUAGGGGCUGCAGGGACAAACAUCGUUGGGGGGUGAGUGUGAAAGGUGCUGAUGGCCCUCAUCUCCAGCUAACUGUGGAGAAGCCCCUGGGGGCUCCCUGAUUAAUGGAGGCUUAGCUUUCUGGAUGGCAUCUAGCCAGAGGCUGGAGACAGGUGCGCCCCUGGUGGUCACAGGCUGUGCCUUGGUUUCCUGAGCCACCUUUACUCUGCUCUAUGCCAGGCUGUGCUAGCAACACCCAAAGGUGGCCUGCGGGGAGCCAUCACCUAGGACUGACUCGGCAGUGUGCAGUGGUGCAUGCACUGUCUCAGCCAACCCGCUCCACUACCCGGCAGGGUACACAUUCGCACCCCUACUUCACAGAGGAAGAAACCUGGAACCAGAGGGGGCGUGCCUGCCAAGCUCACACAGCAGGAACUGAGCCAGAAACGCAGAUUGGGCUGGCUCUGAAGCCAAGCCUCUUCUUACUUCACCCGGCUGGGCUCCUCAUUUUUACGGGUAACAGUGAGGCUGGGAAGGGGAACACAGACCAGGAAGCUCGGUGAGUGAUGGCAGAACGAUGCCUGCAGGCAUGGAACUUUUUCCGUUAUCACCCAGGCCUGAUUCACUGGCCUGGCGGAGAUGCUUCUAAGGCAUGGUCGGGGGAGAGGGCCAACAACUGUCCCUCCUUGAGCACCAGCCCCACCCAAGCAAGCAGACAUUUAUCUUUUGGGUCUGUCCUCUCUGUUGCCUUUUUACAGCCAACUUUUCUAGACCUGUUUUGCUUUUGUAACUUGAAGAUAUUUAUUCUGGGUUUUGUAGCAUUUUUAUUAAUAUGGUGACUUUUUAAAAUAAAAACAAACAAACGUUGUCCUAA